AGCGGAGCCGGCGCCGCCGCCAUGUUGGGUCUGAAGCGGCUGCUGUAGGCGCCGACGGAGCGAGCGGGCGUGCGGAGCGGGCGACAGUGGCGUGGGAUCUGCCUCUCUGCGAGCAGCUGGGAGCGGCGGCGGCGGCGCCAUGAGCGGGGGCACCCCUUACAUCGGCAGCAAGAUCAGCCUCAUCUCCAAGGCGGAGAUCCGCUACGAGGGCAUCCUCUACACCAUCGACACCGAAAACUCCACCGUAGCCCUUGCCAAAGUUCGAUCCUUUGGUACAGAAGACAGACCGACAGAUCGUCCAAUACCACCUCGAGAUGAAGUCUUUGAAUACAUUAUAUUCCGUGGGAGUGACAUUAAAGACCUUACUGUUUGUGAGCCACCAAAACCACAGUGUUCUUUGCCUCAAGACCCAGCUAUUGUUCAGUCCUCACUAGGCUCAUCGACUUCUUCAUUCCAGUCCAUGGGUUCUUAUGGACCUUUCGGCAGGAUGCCCACAUACAGUCAGUUCAGUCCGAGUUCCUUAGUUGGGCAGCAGUUUGGUGCUGUUGGUGUUGCUGGAAGCUCUUUGACAUCCUUUGGAACAGAAACAUCAAACAGUGGUACCUUACCCCAAAGUAGUGCGGUUGGUUCUGCCUUUACACAGGAUACAAGAUCUCUAAAAACACAGUUAUCUCAAGGUCGCUCAAGCCCUCAGUUAGACCCUUUGAGAAAAAGCCCAACCAUGGAACAAGCAGUGCAGACCGCCUCAGCCCACUUACCUGCUCCAGCAGCUGUUGGGAGAAGGAGUCCUGUAUCAACCAGGCCUUUGCCAUCUGCCAGCCAAAAGGCAGGAGAGAAUCAGGAGCACAGGCGAGCUGAAGUACACAAAGUUUCAAGGCCAGAAAAUGAGCAACUCAGAAAUGAUAACAAGAGACAAGUAGCUCCAGGUGCUCCUUCAGCUCCAAGGAGAGGGCGUGGGGGUCAUCGGGGUGGCAGGGGAAGAUUUGGUAUUCGGCGAGAUGGGCCAAUGAAAUUUGAGAAAGACUUUGACUUUGAAAGUGCAAAUGCACAAUUCAACAAGGAAGAGAUUGACAGAGAGUUUCAUAAUAAACUUAAAUUAAAAGAAGAUAAACUUGAGAAACAGGAGAAGCCUGUAAAUGGUGAAGAUAAAGGAGACUCAGGAGUUGAUACCCAAAACAGUGAAGGAAAUGCCGAUGAAGAAGAUCCACUUGGACCUAAUUGCUAUUAUGACAAAACUAAAUCCUUCUUUGAUAAUAUUUCUUGUGAUGACAAUAGAGAACGGAGACCAACCUGGGCUGAAGAAAGAAGAUUAAAUGCUGAAACAUUUGGAAUCCCACUUCGUCCAAACCGUGGCCGUGGGGGAUACAGAGGCAGAGGAGGUCUUGGUUUCCGUGGUGGCAGAGGGCGUGGUGGUGGCAGAGGUGGUACCUUCACUGCCCCUCGAGGAUUUCGCGGUGGAUUCAGAGGAGGUCGUGGGGGCCGGGAGUUUGCGGAUUUUGAAUAUAGGGUAAGUGUUACUGUUAAUAAAUUCUUUGGGGUUGACAUGCAUUUUACAAGACUCAAAACAUUUUUACUUGUUUUUGUUUUGGGUGAAUUGUUUUGAGGACAUUAGAAUAACUUCCAUUUUGACUUUUCAGUAGAGGAUAUACGUGAUUCAGAUGUAUAUAUAAAGACAUUAUACAAAAAAAGACAGUAUAGUAUCACCUUUAUUUCAUGUUAACAGAAUAUACUUUUAACACCCAAAGAGUCUAUCUAGGAAGCACAUACUCCCAGAAUGGAAGGGCAAGCUUUAACAUUUAAUAGCAGUUAACAUUUAUAUAGUAUUUACCAAGUAACAAGACAUUGUUUUAAAUAUUUUUUUACAUAUUAACUUAUUUAAACUGCACAUCAACUCUGUGAGGUAGGUUCUAUUAUUAUCCCCAUUUUACAAGUGAGGAAAUGGGUAUAGAGAUAUUAAGUAACUUGCGAAAGGUCACAUAGCUAGUAAGUGAUGGUGCUGGGUGUUGAGCCCAGCAAGUUGUUUCCUGAGUCAGUACUCUUAAUUUGGUUUUGUUGAAAAUUCACUACAUUUUCCCUGGUUUUCUCCUUUCACCAUGAAAUUGAAAAUGUUUCGAUAUAUUGGCCUUCAGGAGCUACUGCUAGAGAAUUCUGUAACUCUGUAUAGUAGCCUUAUGUGUAUAAUGUAGCUUUUGACAGGUGUCUGUAAAUUAAGUCAGCAUAGUAACUAUCUCAGUUAACAGUAAACUAUCUUAGUUUAUUGAUUUUAGAAGUAGUGGAGAGGAAGGGCUAUAACAGAAAGGACCAAAAUCUUGUAAAGAGUUCCACUUGUAAUAGCAACAGGCAGCUGGAAACAGAAAGACCUGUUAGCAGGAGUUCCAUUGCCCAGUACUUAAAACUGGCCAUUGUUGAGAUCUCUCUGGAAAGAGAUCAGUAUUAGUGGCUUUUGGACCUGCUCUAUUAAUUUUAAUGCUUUUGAUAUUGUGCCAUCACAGCCAAGACUGCCAAAAAUUAUACUCAAGUCACCAGCUUAUGCCAUCCAGCCGUUGGUGGCCUUAUGUAGUUGCGGGACUUCUGACUUGCAAAAUCACCUUCCCAGCUAGGAGAAUCUGUCUUAGGAACUCCAGAAUAGCCCUCGCUUAUCACUGUUACUGCCCUUAAGUUUGCCAGUGACACCUUGCUUACAGAAUUCAGCAGUAGUAUUUUCACAAAUAUUUUAUUUGCCAUUAACUCCUCUGCAAUAUUUGACACUGACCAACCACCCAAUUUGGGGUCUUUCUUCCUAGUCUUUAAAAUACUCUUCUAGGUUUUCAAUUUAUACUCUUCCUAAUUUUUUAAUACUCUUCAUUCUUUUUUUUGGGGGGUGGAGGGUGUCAGGGUCUUGCUGUGUCACCCAGACUGGAGUGCAAUGGCAUGAUCAUAAGUCACUGCAGCCUCAACCUCCCAGGCUCAGGCAGUCCUCCCACCUCAGCCUCCUAUGUAGCUGGGACUACAGGCAUGCACCACCAUGCCCAGCUAAUUUUUAAUUUUUUUUGUAGACACUGGGUCCCACUCUCACUAUGUUGUCCAGGCUGGUCUUGAACUCCUGGGCUUAAGCGAUCCUCUCACCUCAGCUUCCCAAAGUGCUGGGUUUAUAGGUGUGCCAUGGUGCUUGUUCCAUCCUCCCUUUUGUAAGCCUGUCCUGGACCCUAUGUGUUUCUGCACCGCAUCUCUAUCUGCACUGUUUGCUGUCAGCUUAACCUUCCUCAGACUGAUCUCAUCAUCUUCCUUCUCUCCUGUCAUCUCAGCUCUGCCUCCUCCCAGUGUUCCAUGUUGGCUCAUGGUAUACUGCCCAGGCACUAGAGGUAUCCAUGAUUGUGGCCUGUUGCCAUUUAUUCCUUUGAGAUGUCCCUGUCAACUACCAUGGUAACCCACCAGUUGGGCUUCAGACCUUCGUCUCUCUUUACCCCACUUUAAGGCAGAUCAGCUACAUUUUGAACAACCUGUGACAACUCCUUGUUGAAGACCACAUUGAGUCAGCUUGGUCUGAGAAAAAGUACAUUUAAAUUAGACUUGGAUCCAGAUGAGAAUAAUAGCAGUAGUUACUAGUAUGACCUUUCAGACCCUUGGUUUUGACAUUUGUGAAUAAAGAGUUGCACCAUUUAUUCUGAAAUAACACCUUUUAAAGAUCAUUAAACUUUCAGAGUUGGAAAACAUCUGAGAGGUCUGACCUGGUUAAAACAUAAACCUCUUCUGCAGUAUCUCUUAUAGGGGCUGGGAGCUUACUCUUCCCAAGGGCAUCCAUCCCACCCCAGGGAUGUUCUAACUGUUACAAUCUCAGCUGGGCGUGGUGGCUCACACCUAUAAUCCCAGCACUUUGGGAGGCUGAGGUGGGCGGAUCACCUGAGGUCAGGAGUUCGAGACCAGCCUGGCUAACAUGGUGAAACCCCGUCUCUACCAAAAACAUAAAAAAAAUUAGCCGGGCGUGGUGGCACACACCUGUAAUCCCAGCUACUCGGGAGGCUGAGGCAGGAGAAUCAUUGAACCUGGGAGGCAGAGGUUGCAGUGAGCCGAGAUCACGCCACUGUACUCCAGCCUGGGCGACAGAGCAAGACUCCGUCUCAAAAAAAGGAAAAAACAAACCUUCCAUGCAGUAACUGUGUGUGCUCCAUGUGGUUACUAAUACAAACAUUUUUUUGACACCAUGUCACACUGUUUAUCAUUUUGAGCCUUUUGUAAAACUCGUAUCACAUAUAUUGCAGAAUUGAAAAUGCAUUGUCAUAGUUACCUCCAUGCAUCUUUGUCUACGCUCCUGUAUCCUUGACAGAUAGUCCAGCCUCUGCUUAGGUGUUGCCAGGAGUGAUGGACUCAGCGAACCCUCAGGCAUGGCCCAGUGUUUAGGAGGCUCAGUUGUGACAUUGUAGUCCCUGCUCUUCUUAAUUGUGUGAGGAUCCCACUUGAUAUAUUUGGCCUCAUUCCUCAUUACCCUUUAACCUAUCUGAUUCAAGCAAGCUGCCUCAUGGUUAUCUCACAUACACAUUGUGCUUGAUUCCAACUCCAUCCCCAUUCAUUUACCAAAUAUACAGAAUUCUUCAGAUAUGCCAGGCACUAUGUUGAGCAUUGGUGCUGACCGAUGUAGGCCCAGCCCUUUUGAUGUUUACAUUUUGGUGGGAGACAGACAUAGCUAAAAGUCAGGUCCCCCCUUUCACUUAUCCUUUACAGCCUUGCCCAAGUUUUGCUCUGUCUUCUCUUCCUUCCUACACUGAUUUCCUCCUCUUCUGACCUGUGGCUAUCUGCUUUCUUUGGCACACAUUUUAAAUACACUGACAUUCCCUAUUUUUUGUAUUUAGUUUUGUUCUGCAUCACCAGCUAGAUGAGAACCUCUUGGCUUUAGUGAAUAUGUAUUCUACUUUUCUUUCCAUGACAACACUCAGCUCAACAUGGAGCCAUAGUGGGCUUGAAGUAAUUGCUUGUCAUGUUGAUUAGGAAUUUGCCACUCCAGCCUUCAGUGAGACCAAAGGUCUGUCAAUGUAGCUAGCCUUUGAUUGUUCAUUCCAGAGUUGAAUAAUCCUUUCAUCUGCCACUAGAGCCCCGAACCCAGCAGCCCUACACCUCCUAAAUCAUAAAAUCAUUUCACCUGGCACCUUUAAAGGUAGAAAAUGGUGAGUGAUCACUGUCACAUAAAGGAGAUUUACCACUGAAGAUUAAACUUGUAUCUGAAACAUCUAACACUUCCUCCCAGAGAUGGACAUGGAUGACAUUUCUGCAGCCUUCAUGAAAUGAGUUGGCUUUAUUUUUUGUGCUAUAUUAGCAUGAGUCAUUGUGGUUUGGGGGUAAGCAUAAAUGAGCUUGGUUGUUUAAUGAAAACAUGGGUAAAGAUAAAAUCAUAAAGUUUUAGAAUCCUUAAAAGAAUCAGCCAAACUAGAAUCUCUACGCUACCACACUCACAUUAGAUGAUAAGGAAACUAAGGACCCCAAGAAGUUAAUUGUCAUGAUUGAGGUACAAGCUAACAAAUCCAAAACUCACUCUCUUGACUUGUGGCCUGAUUUUCCUUAAGGGUAAUAUUGUAAAUAUAGGCCAGUGCAAUGGUGUACACAUGUAAUACCAGCAUUUUGGGAGGCCAGGGCAGGAUUGCUUAAGCCCAGGAAUUCAAGGACAGCAUGGGCAACAUAAGGAGUCCCUAUCUCUAUAAAAAAGUUUAAAAAUUAGCUGGAGUGGUGGCACAUGCCUGUAGUCCCAGCUACUCAGGAGGCUAAGGCAGGAGGAUCAGUUGAACCUGGGAGGUCAAGGCUGCAGUGAGCCAUGAUCGCACCACUGCACUCCAGCCUGGGUGACAGAGCGAGGCCUGUCUCAAAAAAAAAAAAGAAAAGAAAGAAAUAUAACCUUAUGGUAAGUUUGGUUGUAUGGUGUUUUCCCCCUCCCACCGCCCAUUCUUUUUUGAGGUGAGAAUGGAAAUCAGGACUAGCAAUAAUAAUGUAACCAGCUCCUGUUUUAUAUGCUGCUGUCAGGGAGGUUAAGCCACCAUGGUGGGUGAUAAAAAUCACAUCUGUGUUUCCUCAGAUGGGGUUCAAAGACAACAAGGUGUCUGAAUGACUCAGCAUAAUGCUCUCUCUCCUCUCCCCCUUUCAUUUUCUCCUUUCUCCCUCUCCUGUCCCCAUCUCUUUCUCUUUUUUUUUUUUUUUUUUUUUUUACCUUUCAGAAAACCACAGCUUUUGGACCCUAAAAGGUCUGGAUUGAUCGUACUGCUUUCUGAAAG